AUUAGUCCUUGGCUCUUAUCUUGGAAGCACAGGCGCUGACAGCCGUCCCAGCCCUUCUGUCUGCGGGCCUGAACCAAACGGUGCCAUGGGGAACUGUCUGCACAGGGAGACUCUUCCGGUGUAACUCUGAUGGCCUCCUCUGGGUAUGUCCUCCAGGCGGAGCUCUCCCCCUCAACUGAGAACUCAAGUCAGCUGGACUUCGAAGAUGUAUGGAAUUCUUCCUAUGGUGUGAAUGAUUCCUUCCCAGAUGGAGACUAUGGUGCCAACCUGGAAGCAGCUGCCCCCUGCCACUCCUGUAACCUGCUGGAUGACUCUGCACUGCCCUUCUUCAUCCUCACCAGUGUCCUGGGUAUCCUAGCUAGCAGCACUGUCCUCUUCAUGCUUUUCAGACCUCUCUUCCGCUGGCAGCUCUGCCCUGGCUGGCCUGUCCUGGCACAGCUGGCUGUGGGCAGUGCCCUCUUCAGCAUUGUGGUGCCCGUCUUGGCCCCAGGGCUAGGUAGCACUCGCAGCUCUGCCCUGUGUAGCCUGGGCUACUGUGUCUGGUAUGGCUCAGCCUUUGCCCAGGCUUUGCUGCUAGGGUGCCAUGCCUCCCUGGGCCACAGACUGGGUGCAGGCCAGGUCCCAGGCCUCACCCUGGGGCUCACUGUGGGAAUUUGGGGAGUGGCUGCCCUACUGACACUGCCUGUCACCCUGGCCAGUGGUGCUUCUGGUGGACUCUGCACCCUGAUAUACAGCACGGAGCUGAAGGCUUUGCAGGCCACACACACUGUAGCCUGUCUUGCCAUCUUUGUCUUGUUGCCAUUGGGUUUGUUUGGAGCCAAGGGGCUGAAGAAGGCAUUGGGUAUGGGGCCAGGCCCCUGGAUGAAUAUCCUGUGGGCCUGGUUUAUUUUCUGGUGGCCUCAUGGGGUGGUUCUAGGACUGGAUUUCCUGGUGAGGUCCAAGCUGUUGCUGUUGUCAACAUGUCUGGCCCAGCAGGCUCUGGACCUGCUGCUGAACCUGGCAGAAGCCCUGGCAAUUUUGCACUGUGUGGCUACGCCCCUGCUCCUCGCCCUAUUCUGCCACCAGGCCACCCGCACCCUCUUGCCCUCUCUGCCCCUCCCUGAAGGAUGGUCUUCUCAUCUGGACACCCUUGGAAGCAAAUCCUAGUUCUCUUCCCACCUGUCAACCUGAAUUAAAGUCUACACUGCCUUUGUGAA